GGAAGUCUGGAGGACGCUGAGGGGCGGAGGCGGGAGAGGCGAGCUCGCGAUGAGUGGUCUCGGCAGGCUCUUCGGGAAGGGGAAGAAGGAGAAAGGGCCAACCCCUGAAGAAGCAAUACAGAAACUGAAGGAGACAGAGAAGAUACUGAUCAAGAAACAGGAAUUUUUGGAGCAGAAGAUUCAACAGGAGCUACAAACAGCCAAGAAGUAUGGGACCAAGAAUAAGAGAGCUGCCCUACAGGCUUUGCGGAGGAAGAAAAGAUUCGAACAGCAGCUGGCACAAACUGACGGGACAUUAUCCACCCUGGAGUUUCAGCGUGAGGCCAUUGAGAAUGCCACUACCAAUGCAGAAGUCCUUCGUACCAUGGAGCUUGCUGCCCAAAGCAUGAAGAAGGCCUACCAGGACAUGGACAUUGACAAGGUAGAUGAACUGAUGACUGACAUCACGGAACAACAGGAGGUGGCCCAGCAGAUCUCAGAUGCCAUUUCUCGGCCUAUGGGCUUUGGAGAUGAUGUGGAUGAGGAUGAACUGCUGGAGGAGCUAGAGGAGCUGGAGCAGGAGGAAUUGGCCCAGGAGUUGUUAAAUGUGGGCGACAAGGAAGAAGAACCCUCAGUCAAAUUGCCUAGUGUACCUUCUACUCAUCUGCCGGCAGGGCCAGCUCCCAAAGUGGAUGAAGAUGAAGAAGCACUAAAGCAGUUGGCUGAGUGGGUAUCCUGAUAAAUCUGGGCUUGUCUUCCUAAUGCUACCUUUGUUGGUCCUUUCUUCCUUAAGUGCCAAGUGCUGAGCUAAAGGAGGAUAACUUUUUGGGGAAGUCAUGCUGAGGGUGGUAGUGUGACCCUGCCUGAAAAAAGGGUCUCUUACCCUCCCAGCCCUGGCUCAACUCUGAAGAAGGAUCUUGCUACAGAAGGAGCCCUUGGGCUCCCUUCUCUUUGAUAGCAGUUAUAAUGCCCUUGUUCCCAAUAAAACUGGGCAGAUGGAA